CCUCUUCUAAACAGGUCUGUGGUUUCCUGAAUUGACUGGGAAAGGGUACCAGGGAACUUGUUAGCAUAAUAGAAAUGUUCCAUAUCAUGGUUAUGGUAGUGGUUACAUGGGUGUAUGCAGUUGUCUAAACUUAUUGAACCCUGCACUUAAAAUGGGUAUUUUUUAUCUUAUGUAUGUUAUACCUCAAUAAAGCUGAUGUUUGUAAAAAGAAUAUGUACAACCUAUCCAAUCUACUGUUAAUUGACAUUGAAUUUUUUUCAGUGUUUAGCUACUUCAAACAAUGCAGCUAUGAGUAUUCUUGUAUGUGUACUUUUGUACACAUUUGUACUCAUUUCUAGAGGGUAUGUAUAUCUAGGCAUUGCUGGGUCAUGGGUAUGCAUAUGAUUACAUUUAGUAGAUGCCGCUAAACAGUUUUCUGAGGGGACCGUACCCAUUUACACACUCAGCAACAGUGUAUGAGAGUUCCGCUUGCUCUGUAUCCUCACUGACACUUGCUGUUGUCAGUCUUUGUAAUUUUAAUCAUCCUAGUGGAUGUACAGUGGUGUGGACUAUGGCUUUAAUUUGGAUUUCCUGAAGACUAAUGAGGUUGAUUACCUUUUAUUUGGAUUUUACCUGUCAGUUCUUUUUUUAUUAUUAACUUGUAGGCAUUCUUUAAAUAUUGUGGAUGAGGACUUUGUUAGUGAUAUACUAUUAGCAGGUAAUUCAACCUGUGACUUGCCUUUCAGUUUCGUAUUAGUAAUUUCUAUAAAGGGAAGUUUCUAAUUUUAAUGUCCUCUGAAUGAUCAGUCUUUCCUUUUGUGGUUAAUAGUUUAUGAGUUCUAGGUAAGAAUUUUUUUCUACUCCAUGGUCAUGCAGAUAUCCUCCUGUGUCAUCUUCAAGAUGCGUUAUUCACAAUUAAGCCUAAAGUCCACCUGAAAUUGAUUAUUUUUGCAUAUGAUAUGAGGUCAAGAUGAAUUUUUUUCCUAUGUAGAUAUUUAUUUGGCCCCACACUAUUUUGUGGAAAGUCCAUACUUUCUCUAGAGCUCUGUAAUACCACCUUGAUCAUAAAUUGUAUGUGUGUAGAUCUGUUUCUAGACUUGCUUCUGUUCCAGGGAUUGACCCAUGGCUCAUUUUUGUACAGCCUCCAAGCUAAGAAUAGAUCUGUAUUUUUAUAGGGUUGUUAAAAAAAGAAGAAUAUGCGACGGAGAUUGCAUGUGUCCCAGAAAGCCUAAAAUAUUUACUGUCUGGCUCUUUACAGAAAAAGUUUGCCAACCUUUGUUCUAUUCCAUUGAUCACUUUCUUUGCACCAAAACAACACUAUUUUAAUUAAUGUGGCUUUAUAAUAAGUGCUGCUAUUGGGUAGAAUGUCUUCUUAGAAUCAAAUUUUCAGUUUCUAUACCCACAUGAAAAAAAUUCUGUUGGAAUUUUGAUUUGUUUUAUAUUGUUUAUAAUACUGGAAUAUUUGAAAUAUGGAAUCUUUUGAUCUAUGAAUCUGGUGUAUCUCUCUCAUGAAUGAGUGUUAAAAUGGUCUGCAUCUUUUGGGAUAAUCCUUGGAUUUUUCUUCCUUAAUCACUUAAUGUAGUAGAUCAUGUUGAUAAAGUUUUCAAAUAUGAAACCAGCCCUGCAUUACUGGACUAAACCAAACUUGUCCACAGUGUGUGAUGCUUUUUAUAUAUCACCAGAUUUGGUUUUCUGUUUUAUUUAGAAUUUUUGCAUCUCUGCUCAAGGAUUGCCUUCACCUAAAGUCAGGCCUUGAUCUGAUAAUUGGUGUUGAGUAGCAGACAUCAAGAUGGAAGCAUAAACUAAACCAGGAUGAGAUAUGCAGAAGGCUUAUUGGGGGCAAUGCUUGUAAAGGAUAAAGAAGAAAGCAAGAGAGGACAGGGGAAAACCUGAGACCAUGAGACAGGCCUGACCCCUGUGAAAGAAGAGAGGAAAGGAAAGAAUUGGUAGGAAGGGCCCCAGCCUGCAGCACAGAUCUAAGAAUGCCUCUGCUAGGCCAGUGAAGAGUCCCCAGGCAAACACUUGUCUUUUAGAAGAAUCCUGCUUUGGGCAGGAAUGGGGAAAUGUGGCCUCUGUGUGAACAUGGUGAUGGAUCCAAAGGGCGGCAGCUGGGGCUGUCAGUCACAGUCUUCCCCUCGGCAAGUUCUUCAGAAGGAGGUGUGCAGAGGAACAGCCCACCUCCAUGCUUGACAUGGUUGGCCUUUUUCUUUUCAUCCCUGCUCACAGGUUGUAUUCUUUUGGGGACCCCAAGUGAAAACAUGGUGUUUUCUAGAGCUCUUUUCCUUGGCUGGCCCUGAAGUUCCUUUUUUUUUUUGUCUCCUCAGCCUUUUGAGAUUGAUGGAAGCUCUGUGCAGCUGGUCAGUCUCUCAGCCAUUACUUUGGAAACAGGAAACGCCUCAAGGAAAACAAAGAAACCGCUUGGAACCAAUGGAUACCAUAUUUGUUAAGCAAGUUAAAGAAGGAGGACCUGCUUUUGAAGCUGGAUUAUGUACAGGUGACCGAAUUAUAAAAGUCAAUGGAGAAAGUGUUAUUGGCAAAACCUAUUCCCAAGUAAUUGCUUUAAUUCAAAACAGUGAUACAACAUUGGAACUUAGUGUUAUGCCAAAAGAUGAAGACAUUCUCCAAGUGCUACAGUUUACAAAGGAUGUCACAGCACUGGCAUAUUCUCAAGAUGCCUACCUGAAAGGCAACGAAGCUUAUAGCGGCAAUGCCCGCAAUAUACCUGAACCUCCACCAAUCUGCUAUCCCUGGCUGCCAUCUGCCCCAUCAGCCAUGGCACAGCCAGUUGAAAUAUCUCCUCCUGACUCAUCAUUGAGCAAACAGCAAACCAGUACACCAGUACUGACACAACCUGGUAGGGCCUAUAGAAUGGAAAUACAAGUGCCUCCAUCACCAACAGAUGUUGCAAAAUCAAACACAGCAGUGUGUGUUUGCAAUGAAAGUGUAAGGACUGUCAUUGUGCCUUCUGAGAAGGUUGUAGAUUUGUUAUCCAAUAGAAACAACCAUACAGGUCCUUCACAUAGAACUGAAGAAGUGAGGUAUGGCGUGAGUGAGCAGACCUCUUUAAAAACAGUGUCAAGAACCACAUCACCACCAUUAUCAAUUCCCACCACUCAUCUAAUUCAUCAGCCUGCAGGCUCCAGAUCACUGGAACCUUCUGGAAUUUUACUUAAGUCUGGAAAUUACAGUGGACAUUCUGAUGGAAUCUCAAGCAGCAGAUCUCAAGCUGUGGAGGCUCCCUCUGUAUCUGUUAAUCACUAUUCGCCAAAUUCCCAUCAGCACAUAGACUGGAAAAACUAUAAAACUUACAAAGAGUAUAUUGAUAACAGACGAUUGCACAUAGGUUGUCGGACAAUACAAGAAAGAUUAGAUAGUUUAAGAGCAGCAUCUCAAAGCACGACAGAUUAUAACCAGGUCGUCCCCAACCGCACUACUUUGCAGGGACGACGUCGAAGCACCUCUCAUGAUCGAGUGCCCCAGUCUGUCCAGAUACGGCAACGCAGUGUGUCCCAAGAAAGACUGGAAGAUUCUGUGCUAAUGAAGUAUUGUCCAAGAAGUGCAUCUCAAGGAGCACUGACGUCUCCAUCUGUUAGUUUUAGUAAUCAUAGAACUCGUUCAUGGGAUUAUAUUGAGGGACAGGAUGAAACCUUAGAAAAUGUCAAUUCUGGAACUCCAAUACCUGAUUCCAAUGGAGAGAAAAAACAGACUUACAAGUGGAGUGGGUUUACUGAACAGGAUGAUAGACGAGGUAUUUGUGAAAGACCUAGGCAGCAAGAAAUUCAUAAAUCUUUUCGAGGUUCCAAUUUUACUGUGGCUCCAAGCGUUGUUAAUUCUGAUAACAGGCGAAUGAGUGGUAGAGGAGUGGGAUCUGUGUCGCAGUUUAAAAAAAUUCCACCAGAUCUAAAAACAUUGCAGUCAAACAGAAAUUUUCAGACUACUUGUGGAAUGUCACUGCCUCGGGGUAUUUCACAAGACAGGUCACCUCUUGUGAAAGUCCGAAGUAAUUCUCUGAAAGCUCCUUCCACGCAUGUCACAAAACCAUCAUUUAGCCAGAAAUCAUUUGUUUCUAUCAAAGACCAAAGACCAGUAAAUCACUUGCAUCAGAACAGUCUGUUGAAUCAGCAGACAUGGGUAAGGACUGACAGUGCCCCCGAUCAGCAAGUGGAGACUGGGAAAUCCCCCUCUUUAUCUGGAGCCUCUGCCAAGCCUGCCCCUCAGUCGAGUGAAAACGCUGGUACUUCAGAUUUAGAACUACCUGUCAGUCAAAGGAAUCAAGAUUUAAGUUUACAAGAGGCUGAAACUGAGCAAUCAGAUACUUUAGAUAAUAAAGAAGCUGUCAUCCUAAGGGAAAAACCUCCAUCUGGACGCCAGACACCGCAGCCUUUAAGGCAUCAGUCUUACAUCUUGGCAGUAAAUGACCAGGAGACCGGGUCAGACACUACCUGCUGGCUGCCCAAUGAUGCACGUCGAGAGGUCCACAUAAAAAGAAUGGAGGAAAGAAAAGCCUCGAGUACCAGUCCGCCUGGCGAUUCUUUGGCUUCCAUCCCAUUUAUAGUAAAAGGAAUUUAUUAUAAAGAAUGCAACAAUACUGAAAUGAGUAAGCCCAAUGUUAGUCUCUUCUCCCACGCCUUCUCCAUUCAGUCCUCCUUUAGAACAGAUGAACCAACUAGCCCUAGCAUUGAUCAUGAUAUUGCACAUAUCCCUGCCUCUGCUGUUAUAUCAGCCUCUACCUCUCAGGUCCCCUCCAUAGCAACAGUUCCUCCUUGCCUCACAACUUCAGCUCCAUUAAUUCGCCGUCAGCUCUCACAUGACCACGAAUCUGUUGGCCCUCCUAGCCUGGAUGCUCAGCCCAACUCAAAGACAGAAAGAUCAAAAUCAUAUGAUGAGGGUCUGGAUGAUUACAGAGAAGAUGCAAAAUUGUCCUUUAAGCACGUAUCUAGUCUGAAGGGAAUCAAGAUCGCAGACAGCCAAAAGUCAUCAGAAGACUCUGGGUCCAGAAAAGAUUCUUCCUCAGAGGUCUUCAGUGAUGCUGCCAAGGAAGGGUGGCUUCAUUUCCGACCCCUUGUCACCGAUAAGGGCAAGCGAGUUGGUGGAAGUAUUCGGCCAUGGAAACAGAUGUAUGUUGUCCUUCGGGGUCAUUCACUUUACCUGUACAAAGAUAAAAGAGAGCAGACGACUCCGUCUGAGGAAGAGCAGCCCAUCAGUGUUAAUGCUUGCUUGAUAGACAUCUCUUACAGUGAGACCAAGAGGAAAAAUGUGUUUCGACUCACCACGUCCGACUGUGAAUGCCUGUUUCAGGCUGAAGACAGAGAUGAUAUGCUAGCUUGGAUCAAGACGAUCCAGGAGAGCAGCAACCUAAACGAAGAGGACACUGGAGUCACUAACAGGGAUCUAAUUAGUCGAAGAAUAAAAGAAUACAACAAUCUGAUGAGCAAAGCAGAACAGUUGCCAAAAACACCUCGCCAGAGUCUCAGCAUCAGGCAAACUUUGCUUGGUGCUAAAUCAGAGCCAAAGACUCAAAGCCCACACUCUCCGAAGGAAGAGUCGGAAAGGAAACUUCUCAGUAAAGAUGAUACCAGUCCCCCAAAAGACAAAGGCACAUGGAGAAAAGGCAUUCCAAGUAUCAUGAGAAAGACAUUUGAGAAAAAGCCAACUGCUACAGGAACUUUCGGCGUCCGACUAGAUGACUGCCCACCAGCUCAUACUAAUCGGUAUAUUCCAUUAAUAGUUGACAUAUGUUGCAAAUUAGUUGAAGAAAGAGGUCUUGAAUAUACAGGUAUUUAUAGAGUUCCUGGAAAUAAUGCAGCCAUCUCAAGUAUGCAAGAAGAACUCAACAAGGGAAUGGCUGAUAUUGAUAUACAAGAUGAUAAAUGGCGAGAUUUGAAUGUGAUAAGCAGUUUACUAAAAUCCUUCUUCAGAAAACUCCCUGAGCCUCUCUUCACAAAUGAUAAAUAUGCUGAUUUUAUUGAAGCCAAUCGUAAAGAAGAUCCUCUAGAUCGUCUGAAAACAUUAAAAAGACUAAUUCACGAUUUGCCUGAACAUCAUUAUGAAACACUUAAGUUCCUUUCAGCUCAUCUGAAGACAGUGGCAGAAAAUUCAGAAAAAAAUAAGAUGGAACCAAGAAACCUAGCAAUAGUGUUUGGUCCCACCCUUGUUCGAACAUCAGAAGACAACAUGACCCACAUGGUCACCCACAUGCCUGACCAGUACAAGAUUGUAGAAACGCUCAUCCAGCACCAUGACUGGUUUUUCACAGAAGAAGGUGCUGAAGAGCCUCUUACAACAGUGCAGGAGGAAAGCACAGUAGACUCCCAGCCAGUGCCAAACAUAGAUCAUUUACUCACCAACAUUGGAAGGACAGGAGUCUCCCCAGGAGAUGUAUCAGAUUCAGCUACUAGUGACUCAACAAAAUCUAAGGGUUCUUGGGGAUCUGGAAAGGAUCAGUAUAGCAGGGAACUGCUUGUGUCCUCCAUCUUUGCAGCUGCUAGUCGCAAGAGGAAGAAGCCGAAAGAAAAAGCACAGCCUAGCAGCUCAGAAGAUGAACUGGACAAUGUAUUUUUUAAGAAAGAAAAUGUGGAACAGUGUCACAAUGAUACUAAAGAGGAGUCCAAAAAAGAAAGUGAGACACUGGGCAGAAAACAGAAGAUCAUCAUUGCCAAAGAAAACAGCACUAGGAAAGACCCCAGCACGACAAAAGAUGAAAAGAUAUCACUAGGAAAAGAGAGCACGCCUUCUGAAGAACCCUCACCACCACACAACUCAAAACACAACAAGUCACCAACUCUCAGCUGUCGCUUUGCCAUCCUGAAAGAGAGCCCCAGGUCACUUCUGGCACAGAAGUCCUCCCACCUUGAAGAGACAGGCUCUGACUCUGGCACUUUGCUCAGCACGUCUUCCCAGGCCUCCCUGGCAAGGUUUUCCAUGAAGAAAUCAACCAGUCCAGAAACGAAACAUAGCGAGUUUUUGGCCAACGUCAGCACCAUCACCUCAGAUUAUUCCACCACAUCGUCUGCUACAUACUUGACUAGCCUGGACUCCAGUCGACUGAGCCCUGAGGUGCAAUCCGUGGCAGAGAGCAAGGGGGACGAGGCAGAUGACGAGAGAAGCGAACUCAUCAGUGAAGGGCGGCCUGUGGAAACCGACAGCGAGAGCGAGUUUCCCGUGUUCCCCACAGCCUUGACUUCAGAGAGGCUUUUCCGAGGAAAACUGCAAGAAGUGACUAAGAGCAGCCGGAGAAAUUCUGAAGGAAGUGAAUUAAGUUGCACCGAGGGAAGUUUAACAUCAAGUUUAGAUAGCCGGAGACAGCUCUUCAGUUCCCAUAAACUCAUCGAAUGUGAUACUCUUUCCAGGAAAAAAUCAGCUAGAUUCAAGUCAGAUAGUGGAAGUCUAGGAGAUGCCAAGAAUGAGAAAGAAGCACCUUCGUUAACUAAAGUGUUUGAUGUUAUGAAAAAAGGAAAGUCAACUGGGAGUUUACUGACACCCACCAGAGGCGAAUCCGAAAAACAGGAACCCACAUGGAAAACGAAAAUAGCAGAUCGGUUAAAACUGAGACCCAGAGCCCCUGCGGAUGACAUGUUUGGAGUAGGGAAUCACAAAGUGAAUGCCGAGACUGCUAAAAGGAAAAGCAUCCGGCGCAGACAUACACUAGGAGGGCACAGAGAUGCUACCGAAAUCAGCGUUUUGAAUUUUUGGAAAGUGCAUGAGCAGAGCGGGGAGAGAGAAUCUGAACUUUCAGCUGUAAACCGGUUAAAACCAAAAUGCUCAGCCCAGGACCUUUCCAUCUCAGACUGGCUGGCCAGGGAACGCCUACGCACCAGUACCUCUGACCUUAGCAGAGGAGAAAUCGGAGAUCCCCAGACAGAGAACCCAAGCACACGAGAAAUAGCCACGACCGACACACCUUUGUCUCUUCAUUGCAACACAGGCAGUUCUUCCAGCACCUUGGCUUCAACAAACAGGCCCCUUCUUUCCAUACCACCACAGUCACCUGACCAAAUAAACGGAGAAAGCUUCCAGAACGUGAGCAAAAAUGCUAGUUCUGCAGCGAAUGCCCAACCUCAUAAACUGUCUGAAACCCCAGGCAGUAAAGCAGAGUUUCAUCCCUGUCUUUAAACUGGGGGUAUGUCCACUCUAGCAAGUAAAAAAACUACUGUUACACGUUCCAGUAACUCUGUCAAUAUUUUCUUGUAUCAGAAUUGUUAUUAUGCAGCCUUCAUUUGGGCUGGUUUCAUCAUUUUGCACUGUGAAAUAGCUUUACAGUGCAUUACUACAGCCAGAAGAACAUAUAUAUAUAUAUAUAUAUUUAAAAAUAUAUCGGAUAGUUGUAUACAAAUGAGCAAGGUAUUUGUUGCAACUUACUACAUAGCAUAUACCCAAAAUCACUGAAGAAAAUCGCUGGCAUCAGUGUGCAGCAAAUUUGUUCUUUUGGUUUCAUCACUAACAAAAGUGCCUCAUCAUAAAAAUACAGUUGGUUUUUAGGGUGCCAUAUUGUUAAAAUUAGAUAACUUACUUACAUUGAAUAAACGAAUGCGUUUUAUUGGUAACAGAUAUCAUUACAUUUACCAGUUUUAACACAGGUGGAUACAGAACUUCCAUUCUUUAGUCAUUCCAGGUGGAUCUGAGUUUUAUAUUCAAACUUUUAAUACAGUUUUUGAGUUUUGUGUGACUUGAAUUUUUAAUCUUUCUGUAAAAUACGUAACUUAAAUGAACAUAUUAAAUGUGUAUCUUUUCUUCAGAUACCAGAUUUGAUAUAAUGUUGUAACAUAGGUGUGUAGAUAGUGGAUCCUGGAUGGAACUGGCUUCUUUAUCGAGAAGAAUAUAAUUCUGCAUGAGGACUUAAUGAAUCCAAACCUGUGUCAUGCCUGUGUGCAUACCCAAUUAAACACUGGAAAUAAAAAUUGUUUUGGUGAA